AGAACAGAGUGAGCAGCCUUGCCCUGAGUCAUUUCACCUAAAAGGAAAGAGAAUUAAGGAGUUGCCUUCAAUGGUAAGUUCCAGAAAAAGCAUCAGACUAGAAAAUGAAGAGCUGCCAGAACCCCCGCAAGUUAGCAGGGAUGUGUAUUAUGCCUGGCAUGGCAAUGGAAAGGGUGCUCUUGGUUUUGUGGAAUCCACUUGAUUGUAAAUAAAUGUGUUAUAUUUAGGACUGUAUAAUUUUGAAGUCAGAAGGAUGAAGAGUUGUUCAAACUCAGAGUGGAGGCCCAGAGACAUUUAAGAGGAAAGUAGAAAGAAGCCUGUUUCUGACCAGCCCUCUUCCUCCACCCCUCCUGCCCAGGGGGGUAUCUCUAGUUUCCCCUCUAAAGUAGCUGGGGCCCUGCUGCGUUUCUCUCUUAUAGGCACAUGGCUCAGAGAAUUGGGGAUUCAGAAUGUUCUUUCUGGUGUUCUGACCAUUGACAACUUAUGAUAUGCUCAUUUUUCCUUAGGAGCUAAAGGAUCUGACACCUUUCACAUUAUGAAUUCACUUUGAAAGCACUGUUUCCUUCUUUGUUUAAACUCCAAGAGGCAGUAGAGCAUGGUGUUAGGAGCCCAAACUCUGGAGUCAACCUGACCAAGUGACCAUGGAUUUUGAGUAUUCCAGGAAGUAAAUUAUGCCUAUAAUAGAGUGGGCAUGUGGCGUAUCCAUACAGGUAAUUUUUUUUAAUGAAAUACUGCAAAGCCCCUGGCUUUAGAUUACAAUUAAUGACAAAGCCUACCAGAUUUUAUGAUUUGAAUACACAUGUAAAAGCAAUACAUAUUGAGGCUGGUACUUUGUGAAUUGACUCACAAUAUUGUGAAUAUAUUCCAUGGAGGUAUAAAAUCACAGGAAAAAUGAGUUUAUUAAUGGAAAUUAGGCUAGAUCCUGAUUAUUACCUGUGAAUAGUGUCAUCAUUUGAAGUUUUUAUUGCAUUUUAACACAUGGCUUAUCUUGAUGAGAAAAUAUAUAGCAAAGGGUAAACGUAGCAAUUUUCCUUUUACUAUUCCCUCCGCUAAGCCAUUAUUGCUUGAUGUUAUUUUUCAGCAGCCUUUCAUUUUUGUCCCAAAUGUUUUUGCCUCUGGCUGGUUUUAUUUCUUUAAAAUGUAUGUGUAUCACUUCUCAAAAUGAUACAUUUUGACAGGUAAUCGAUAUUUUUUCAUACUAGAUUUGAUGGUAUGAUGGUCAUAAUCCUCAUUUUAGACUUAGUUAAUGGUGGAACACUCACUUAGAUUUUAUCUCAAAAUAUUCCUUUGUUAAGAAACAUACUUUUCGUCCUUAGCCAGAUUCCUAUUUAUCACUCCCACCACCUCCCAAACACCUCGAGCUGCAGAGUGCCUAAGAUGCAUGCACGUCAGCUGACAUUUUGACAGUGUGUCCUCGAAAUGUCUUCUGAUAGUACUUCCAACUAGCUUACACGAUUGGUCACAGAAAAGAUACUUCUGGGCUCUCUACCUGUUUUGUUUUGUUCUCCUGAUGACCCGAUUUGUGUUUCAAGGGGAAAACUGGUUUGUCCUCCCACCACCCCCCCCAAUCCCCCGUCUCUUUCUCUGUAGUGGGAAUUUGUUGCCCUCCUCUAGACCCUAGUUUUUCUAGAAGGACCAGCACAAUGAAGAUUGUAGUCCUCAGAGUAGAAGUGUAUAUGAGUACACCAUGCUUGGCUUUUGCUUUUAAAAAUUGAGCUUCUUGGGUCAAGAUUUUUUCCAAAAUCUGUCAGGACUUCCUUUUGCCUCUGUGGGCAGAUAGCAAUGACACUGUAAGCUGGUAAAUAUAUUCGGAGCUGCUGCCAAGGCUUUGUCUAAAACAACUCUUGACAUUCAGGGAACUUUCUGUGCUCCUCUCUCAGGAGGGUGACUUGAGAUAGAAAGCAGGCAACAAUUGUCGUUCCCUUCGUUUUCACUGAAGAGCCAGAUUUUCUCUUUGCAGGAACAGAUUAAAGUGCAGGUGAGCCUGUGAAGGUUGGGGGUCUGUUCUCCACCAGCAUUACAGAUUGCCAAAAGAUAGAACAAGGCUGGCCCUUUCUCCUCUCUUAAGUGGCUUUUGUUUCUUUUAUUUUUGUCCUUUGAUUUAAACAAAAAACGUAGUUUUAAAAAUCUUUUUUAAAAAUUCAUUUGUGCUAGAAUUCGUUGAUACACUUUGACUUGAAGAAUGACCAGUUUUUGUGCUGUAUUUUGCUUUAGAGAUGAUAUUACUCCUCCACAUAUAAGCGAGAGCUAAAAACUCUCUGGGGUUUUCUUCCUUAAGUGGUAUCAAAUCAACAUGCCUAAGUGGAAAAACACCCUGACACCCUUCUCUGCUGGGGUGGCAUUUCUUGACAGGCUCCUCUUUGUAUGUCUGGAGAUAUAUGCAAAGACCGUUUGGGAACAUAAAAUGCAAUCAAUUUUCCUCAGUGGUUAGAUUCAUAAAUCCCUGAGCUAUUUUUAAUGACAUAAUCUAAUCAAUUGAGAGCAAGCGUAUUAGUGUGUUGACAGACAGAAAGAGAUGGAAAACCAGUGGAAUAGCAGGUGAAUGGGUAGGGAACCACUAGACACUUCCUUCCCCUCUCCCACAUUUAAACAUCACUAGAUAACUGGGUUAAGUAAAAUCCAGGAGUUAGUGAUUUAAAAAAAUGUUUAUACCUGUCUUCCUAACUUUCAAGAAAAAUAAUUAUUCUAAUGGAUAGAGUGAAAGAGGUCGUUCUUAGACAAAGUACAGUUGGUCCUUGUAUCUCUCUCAGGAUCAAACUAUUCUCUCAAUUUAAAUAUCUUUAGAAUAGACACCAAGGAGGAAUAAUUUAUUAUGAAUUGGUAGUGUCGUAUGUUGUUACUCCUGUGCCAUGCCAGUAAUGAAAACUUAAUAUUCAUCUCUUGGUUGCUUUCAAUUGAGAUAAGAUGAGGAUGAACGGAGUAAACAAGCUGAGACAGACUGUGAAAUUGCACGAUGGGAAUUUUUUCUUUAGCUGCUUAUACACUAUACAUAGGUUAAAUAUUCCAACUAAUGAUGGCUCUUAGAAUCCCCUCCACCCAACCUUUUUACAUUUUGGUCAGGUAUCAGCAGAACUAAGUUAUUAUCAUGAGGGAAAUUAAACUGUUUCUGUCUUUGAGCUAGUAGGAACUGAAGGGCAGGUAUUUAUGUAAAUGAAUGGGCUUUCAUGCUGGGAGGUGUAAAGGGUUUGGUGGCUGGAGAGCAGCUGCCCUGAGCCCUCCGUUUUCAGGUUUGCAGGCAGCAUGUGUGUUCUGCUACAUUUUUGUUUUCUUUGAUGCCUUUGGAAGAGAUGAGCGCCAGGCAUAGUGGUGCUGCUUGGCUGACCAGCUGUGCCCUAGUUUUUCACCAUCCCAGUCAGCGGCUGCCUUUUACAGAGGUGUCUGUCACCGCUGAUUUACUUAGCCACUGUGACCUUAUAGUUGCUUCAGAUGGGGCUUGACCCAAAGCUACUGCCGAAAGCCAUUUAGUGGUCUCCUGAAAUGCCACAGCCAGCAUUCUGAAGAAGAGAAAACAAGGAUCUCACGAUUUCCUGUCUAAUAGCAAGAGCCUCCUCCACCUGGAUAAAUGCAUUAGGUGUCUGAGCCCACUUGCUGCUCUCUCCCACCGAACUGCAAGCAUCCGUGAUCUCCGAAGUUGCUGGAGUGAAUAACUAAGCUGGACCAGCUGACUCCGGGCUCCAAUCAGCUAGAGCGUGAUAAGGAGCUGAGUCUCCCCAGAAGAGGAAGUUUUUGCCGAACAAGCAACCGGAAAAGCUUAAUAGGCAAUGGGCAGUCACCAGCAUUGCCUCGACCACACUCACCUCUCUCUGCUCAUGCAGGAAAUAGCCCUCAAGAUAGUCCAAGAAAUUUCUCCCCCAGUGCCUCAGCCCAUUUUUCAUUUGCACGGAGGACUGAUGGACGCCGCUGGUCGUUGGCUUCUCUCCCUUCCUCUGGCUAUGGGACAAACACACCCAGCUCUACGGUCUCUUCAUCCUGUUCCUCCCAGGAGAAGUUGCAUCAGUUACCAUACCAACCAACACCAGACGAGUUACACUUCUUAUCAAAACAUUUCUGUACCACCGAAAGCAUCGCCACUGAGAACAGAUGCAGGAACACGCCGAUGCGCCCCCGUUCCCGAAGUCUGAGCCCUGGACGUUCUCCCGCCUGCUGUGACCAUGAAAUAAUUAUGAUGAACCAUGUCUACAAAGAAAGGUUCCCAAAGGCUACAGCUCAGAUGGAAGAACGUCUAAAGGAAAUUAUCACCAGCUACUCUCCUGACAACGUUCUACCCUUAGCAGAUGGAGUGCUUAGUUUCACUCACCACCAGAUUAUUGAACUGGCUCGAGAUUGCUUGGAUAAAUCCCACCAGGGCCUCAUCACCUCACGAUACUUCCUUGAAUUACAGCACAAAUUAGAUAAGUUGCUACAGGAGGCUCAUGAUCGUUCAGAAAGUGGAGAAUUGGCAUUUAUUAAACAACUAGUUCGAAAGAUCCUAAUUGUUAUUGCCCGCCCUGCUCGGUUAUUAGAGUGCCUGGAAUUUGAUCCGGAAGAAUUUUACUACCUAUUGGAAGCAGCAGAAGGCCAUGCCAAAGAAGGACAGGGUAUUAAAACCGACAUUCCCAGGUACAUCAUUAGCCAACUGGGACUCAAUAAGGAUCCCUUGGAAGAAAUGGCUCAUUUGGGAAACUACGAUAGUGGGACAGCAGAAACACCAGAAACAGAUGAAUCAGUGAGUAGCUCUAAUGCCUCCCUGAAACUUCGAAGGAAACCUCGGGAAAGUGAUUUUGAAACGAUUAAAUUGAUUAGCAAUGGAGCCUAUGGGGCAGUCUACUUUGUUCGGCAUAAAGAAUCCCGGCAGAGGUUUGCCAUGAAGAAGAUUAAUAAACAGAACCUCAUCCUUCGAAACCAGAUCCAGCAGGCCUUUGUGGAGCGGGAUAUCCUGACUUUUGCAGAAAACCCCUUUGUUGUCAGCAUGUAUUGCUCCUUUGAAACAAGGCGCCACUUGUGCAUGGUCAUGGAAUAUGUGGAAGGGGGAGACUGUGCUACUUUAAUGAAAAACAUGGGUCCUCUCCCUGUUGAUAUGGCCAGAAUGUACUUUGCUGAGACGGUCUUGGCCUUGGAAUAUUUACAUAAUUAUGGAAUUGUACACAGGGAUUUGAAACCAGACAACUUGUUGGUUACCUCCAUGGGGCACAUAAAGCUGACAGAUUUUGGAUUAUCUAAGGUGGGACUAAUGAGCAUGACUACCAACCUUUACGAGGGUCAUAUUGAGAAGGAUGCUAGAGAGUUCCUGGAUAAACAGGUCUGUGGCACACCUGAAUACAUUGCACCAGAAGUGAUUCUGAGGCAGGGUUAUGGAAAGCCGGUGGACUGGUGGGCCAUGGGGAUUAUCCUCUAUGAAUUUCUGGUUGGAUGCGUGCCAUUCUUUGGGGAUACUCCAGAGGAGCUAUUUGGACAAGUCAUCAGUGAUGAGAUCAACUGGCCUGAGAAGGAUGAGGCACCCCCACCUGAUGCCCAGGAUCUGAUUACCUUACUCCUCAGGCAGAAUCCCCUGGAGAGGCUGGGAACAGGUGGUGCAUAUGAAGUCAAACAGCAUCGAUUCUUCCGUUCUUUAGACUGGAACAGUUUGCUGAGACAGAAGGCAGAAUUUAUUCCCCAACUGGAAUCUGAGGAUGACACAAGUUAUUUUGAUACUCGGUCUGAGAAGUAUCAUCAUAUGGAAACGGAGGAAGAAGAUGACACAAAUGAUGAAGACUUUAAUGUGGAAAUAAGGCAGUUUUCUUCAUGUUCACACAGGUUUUCAAAAGUUUUCAGCAGUAUAGAUCGAAUCACUCAGAAUUCAGCAGAAGAGAAGGAAGACUCUGUGGACAAAACCAAAAGCACCACCUUGCCAUCCACAGAAACACUGAGCUGGAGUUCAGAAUAUUCUGAAAUGCAACAGCUAUCAACAUCCAACUCUUCAGAUACUGAAAGCAACAGACAUAAACUCAGUUCUGGCCUACUUCCCAAACUGGCUAUUUCAACAGAGGGAGAGCAAGAUGAAGCUGCCUCCUGCCCUGGAGACCCCCAUGAGGAGCCAGGAAAGCCAGCCCUUCCUCCUGAAGAGUGUGCCCAGGAGGAGCCUGAGGUCACCACCCCAGCCAGCACCAUCAGCAGCUCCACCCUGUCAGUUGGCAGUUUUUCAGAGCACUUGGAUCAGAUAAAUGGACGAAGCGAGUGUGUGGACAGUACAGAUAAUUCCUCAAAGCCAUCCAGUGAACCCGCUUCUCACAUGGCUCGGCAGCGAUUAGAAAGCACAGAAAAAAAGAAAAUCUCGGGGAAAGUCACAAAGUCCCUCUCUGCCAGUGCUCUUUCCCUCAUGAUCCCAGGAGAUAUGUUUGCUGUUUCCCCUCUGGGAAGUCCAAUGUCUCCCCAUUCCCUGUCCUCGGACCCUUCUUCUUCACGAGAUUCCUCUCCCAGCCGAGAUUCCUCAGCAGCUUCUGCCAGUCCACAUCAGCCGAUUGUGAUCCACAGUUCGGGGAAGAACUACGGCUUUACCAUCCGAGCCAUCCGGGUGUAUGUGGGAGACAGUGACAUCUAUACAGUGCACCAUAUCGUCUGGAAUGUAGAAGAAGGAAGUCCGGCAUGCCAGGCAGGACUGAAGGCUGGAGAUCUUAUCACUCACAUCAAUGGAGAACCAGUGCAUGGACUUGUCCACACAGAAGUUAUAGAACUCCUACUGAAGAGUGGGAAUAAGGUGUCAAUCACUACUACCCCAUUUGAAAACACAUCAAUCAAAACUGGACCAGCCAGGAGAAACAGCUAUAAGAGCCGGAUGGUGAGGCGGAGCAAGAAAUCCAAGAAGAAAGAAAGUCUCGAAAGGAGGAGAUCUCUUUUCAAAAAGCUAGCCAAGCAGCCUUCUCCUUUACUCCACACCAGCCGAAGUUUCUCCUGCUUGAACAGAUCCCUGUCAUCGGGUGAGAGCCUCCCAGGUUCCCCCACUCAUAGCUUGUCUCCCCGGUCUCCAACACCAAGCUACCGCUCCACCCCUGACUUCCCAUCUGGUACUAAUUCCUCCCAGAGCAGCUCCCCUAGUUCUAGUGCCCCCAAUUCCCCAGCAGGGUCCGGGCACAUCCGGCCCAGCACUCUCCACGGUCUUGCACCCAAACUCGGCGGGCAGCGGUACCGGUCCGGAAGGCGAAAGUCCGCCGGCAACAUCCCACUGUCCCCGCUGGCCCGGACGCCCUCUCCAACCCCGCAACCCACCUCCCCGCAGCGGUCACCAUCCCCUCUUCUGGGACACUCACUGGGCAAUUCCAAGAUCGCGCAAGCCUUUCCCAGCAAGAUGCACUCCCCGCCCACCAUCGUCAGACACAUCGUGAGGCCCAAGAGUGCGGAGCCCCCCAGGUCCCCGCUGCUCAAGCGCGUGCAGUCCGAGGAGAAGCUGUCGCCCUCUUACGGCAGUGACAAGAAGCACCUGUGCUCCCGCAAGCACAGCCUGGAGGUGACCCAAGAGGAGGUGCAGCGGGAGCAGUCCCAGCGGGAGGCGCCGCUGCAGAGCCUGGAUGAGAACGUGUGCGACGUGCCGCCGCUCAGCCGCGCCCGGCCAGUGGAGCAAGGCUGCCUGAAACGCCCAGUCUCCCGGAAGGUGGGCCGCCAGGAGUCUGUGGACGACCUGGACCGCGACAAGCUGAAGGCCAAGGUGGUGGUGAAGAAAGCAGACGGCUUCCCAGAGAAACAGGAAUCCCACCAGAAAUCCCAUGGACCCGGGAGUGAUUUGGAAAACUUUGCUCUGUUUAAGCUGGAAGAGAGAGAGAAGAAAGUCUAUCCGAAGGCUGUGGAAAGGUCAAGUACUUUUGAAAACAAAGCGUCUAUGCAGGAGGCGCCACCGCUGGGCAGCCUGCUGAAGGAUGCUCUUCACAAGCAGGCCAGCGUGCGCGCCAGCGAGGGUGCGAUGUCGGAUGGCCGGGUGCCUGCGGAGCACCGCCAGGGUGGCGGGGACUUCAGACGGGCCCCCGCUCCUGGCACCCUCCAGGAUGGUCUCUGCCACUCCCUCGACAGGGGCAUCUCUGGGAAGGGGGAAGGCACGGAGAAGUCCUCCCAGGCCAAGGAGCUUCUCCGAUGUGAAAAGUUAGACAGCAAGCUGGCCAACAUCGAUUACCUCCGAAAGAAAAUGUCACUUGAGGACAAAGAGGACAACCUCUGCCCUGUGCUGAAGCCCAAGAUGACAGCUGGCUCCCACGAAUGCCUGCCAGGGAACCCAGUCCGACCCACGGGUGGGCAGCAGGAGCCCCCGCCGGCUUCUGAGAGCCGAGCUUUUGUCAGCAGCACCCAUGCAGCUCAGAUGAGUGCCGUCUCUUUUGUUCCCCUCAAGGCCUUAACAGGCCGGGUGGACAGUGGAACGGAGAAGCCUGGCUUGGUUGCUCCUGAGUCCCCUGUUAGGAAGAGCCCCUCCGAGUAUAAGCUGGAAGGUAGGUCUGUCUCAUGCCUGAAGCCGAUCGAGGGCACUCUGGACAUUGCUCUCCUGUCCGGACCUCAGGCCUCCAAGACAGAACUGCCUUCCCCAGAGUCUGCACAGAGCCCCAGCCCAAGUGGUGACGUGAGGGCCUCUGUGCCACCAGUUCUCCCCAGCAGCAGUGGGAAAAAGAACGAUACCACCAGUGCAAGAGAGCUUUCUCCUUCCAGCUUAAAGAUGAAUAAAUCCUACCUGCUGGAGCCUUGGUUCCUGCCCCCCAGCCGAGGUCUCCAGAAUUCACCAGCAGUUUCCCUGCCUGACCCAGAGUUCAAGAGGGACAGGAAAGGUCCCCAUCCUACUGCCAGGAGCCCUGGAACAGUCAUGGAAAGCAAUCCCCAACAGAGAGAGGGCAGCUCCCCUAAACACCAAGACCACACCACUGACCCCAAGCUUCUGACCUGCCUGGGGCAGAACCUCCACAGCCCUGACCUGGCCAGGCCACGCUGCCCGCUCCCACCUGAAGCUUCCCCCUCAAGGGAGAAGCCAGGCCUGAGGGAAUCGUCUGAAAGAGGCCCUCCCACAGCCAGAAGCGAGCGCUCUGCUGCGAGGGCUGACACAUGCAGAGAGCCCUCCAUGGAACUGUGCUUUCCAGAAACUGCGAAAACCAGUGACAACUCCAAAAAUCUCCUCUCUGUGGGAAGGACCCACCCAGAUUUCUAUACACAGACCCAGGCCAUGGAGAAAGCAUGGGCGCCGGGUGGGAAAACGAACCACAAAGAUGGCCCAGGUGAGGCGAGGCCCCCGCCCAGAGACAACUCCUCUCUGCACUCAGCUGGAAUUCCCUGUGAGAAGGAGCUGGGCAAGGUGAGGCGUGGCGUGGAACCCAAGCCCGAAGCGCUUCUUGCCAGGCGGUCUCUGCAGCCACCUGGAAUUGAGAGUGAGAAGAGUGAAAAGCUCUCCAGUUUCCCAUCUUUGCAGAAAGAUGGUGCCAAGGAACCUGAAAGGAAGGAGCAGCCUCUACAAAGGCAUCCCAGCAGCAUCCCUCCGCCCCCUCUGACGGCCAAAGACCUGUCCAGCCCGGCUGCCAGGCAGCAUUGCAGUUCCCCAAGCCACGCUUCUGGCAGAGAGCCGGGGGCCAAGCCCAGCACUGCAGAGCCCAGCUCGAGCCCCCAGGACCCUCCCAAGCCUGUUGCUGCGCACAGUGAAAGCAGCAGCCACAAGCCCCGGCCUGGCCCUGACCCGGGCCCUCCAAAGACUAAGCACCCCGACCGGUCCCUCUCCUCUCAGAAACCAAGUGUCGGGGCCACAAAGGGCAAAGAGCCUGCCACUCAGUCCCUCGGUGGCUCUAGCAGAGAGGGGAAGGGCCACAGUAAGAGUGGGCCGGAUGUGUUUCCUGCUACCCCAGGCUCCCAGAACAAAGCCAGCGAUGGGAUUGGCCAGGGAGAAGGUGGGCCCUCUGUCCCACUGCACACUGACAGGGCUCCUCUAGACGCCAAGCCACAACCCACCAGUGGUGGGCGGCCCCUGGAGGUGCUGGAGAAGCCUGUGCAUUUGCCAAGGCCGGGACACCCAGGGCCUAGUGAGCCAGCGGACCAGAAACUGUCCGCUGUUGGUGAAAAGCAAACCCUGUCUCCAAAGCACCCCAAACCAUCCACUGUGAAAGAUUGCCCCACCCUGUGCAAACAGACAGACAACAGACAGACAGACAAAAGCCCGAGUCAGCCGGCCGCCAACACCGACAGAAGGGCGGAAGGGAAGAAAUGCACUGAAGCACUUUAUGCUCCAGCAGAGGGCGACAAGCUCGAGGCCGGCCUUUCCUUUGUGCAUAGCGAGAACCGGUUGAAAGGCGCGGAGCGGCCAGCCGCGGGGGUGGGGAAGGGCUUCCCUGAGGCCAGAGGGAAAGGGCCCGGUCCCCAGAAGCCACCGACGGAGGCAGACAAGCCCAAUGGCAUGAAACGGUCCCCCUCAGCCACUGGGCAGAGUUCUUUCCGAUCCACGGCCCUCCCGGAAAAGUCUCUGAGCUGCUCCUCCAGCUUCCCUGAAACCAGGGCCGGAGUUAGAGAGGCCUCUGCAGCCAGCAGCGACACCUCUUCUGCCAAGGCCGCCGGGGGCAUGCUGGAGCUUCCAGCCCCCAGCAACAGGGACCAUAGGAAGGCUCAGCCUGCCGGGGAGGGCCGAACCCACAUGACAAAGAGUGACUCCCUGCCCUCCUUCCGGGUCUCCACCCUGCCUCUGGAGUCACACCACCCCGACCCAAACACCAUGGGCGGGGCCAGCCACCGGGACAGGGCUCUCUCGGUGACUGCCACCGUAGGGGAAACCAAAGGGAAGGACCCUGCCCCAGCCCAGCCUCCCCCAGCUAGGAAACAGAACGUGGGCAGAGACGUGACCAAGCCAUCCCCAGCCCCAAACACUGACCGCCCCAUCUCUCUUUCUAAUGAGAAGGACUUUGUGGUACGGCAGAGGCGGGGGAAAGAGAGUUUGCGUAGCAGCCCUCACAAAAAGGCCUUGUAACGGGGAGGGCCCAGGGGCAGGACUGUGGAGACCCGUCCUGAACGGGCGACUGUGUCUUGACUACCUUUCAAAACCAGCACUGUGUGGGAAUGUCCGCCAGGCAGAGCUCGGAGCCUCAUUGAGACAGGGGAGAGAGAAAGACAAAGAGGGGACCUUCUUCCAGAUGCCUUCCCAGUUGUAACCGGUAAAACUGUUACCAGAUAGUGUUUGUACAAAAAAAAAAAAAAAAAAAAAAAAAAAAAUUACCUUUACAGUUGAGGGUUGUUGAGGAAAAUGAUUUUCUUUGUAAAUAUAUAGCAUCGUGUUUGGUUUGGGAUGUAGAGUCUAUACCUGGCUGCUGAUUGCGUCGUUUACUACAGCUUUUUUUAAAUAAGAUUUUUGCUUUACCAUUUAUCAUAAUGUAGUAAUGAAGCAAAAUGGUCAAAACUGGGUGUGUGUGAACAGAGAUACACCCAUAUUCGUGUAUAUACACAUCCACCUACAUGUUUUGGUCUGUGGUUUAAGAGACUAUUUCAAGGUUCCAUUUUUAUAAGCUAAAACAUUCUAAGUUAAGAUGGAAGAAAGCCCUAAACACAGUAGAUUCUGAGUUUUUAUGUGUAUUUUAACCAGAGUUUCUGAUAGUACUGUAUCUGGCUACCUAUAUUUCCAGAUCUAAAGCAAGAACUACUCUAAGUACUGCAUUUGGAAUCCUCCUCCAUUAGGAAUGGCCAGGACAAGUGGAGCUAGCCAUUUUCAUUACACGGCCAUCCCAAUGGACACUGGAUCCCUGGUCCAACUGUCUAAAAGGCCAGUUGUUCCUUUCUGUGGAUGUGGAUGUCUGGCCUUCACCUGAGGUAGAGCGGGGACUAUAAACACACAUCAACUUUCUUUCUGUUUGCUUUCUUUUCCUUCUUUUCAAACUCUUAAACUCAGGCCUUUAUGCUGUGAGUGACUAGUCCAAGAAGCACACAUUUUGUAGUAGUCCUGCACCAGCCCUGCUCUUGAAUAAAAAGGAAAAUUACUGGCUGCACCCAAAUCUUCUAGUACUUGAGUAAUAAGCAUCAGGCAUUGGAAGAGGUUUUAAAUUUGCUUUUUUGAGGAAAAGAACUGGGGGUGGAUUUUGGCAUCGUAGCAUAUCGAUUAAAGAAUAAUCAGGACAUCAGAUACAUUUUAAUACAUAGCUGGGGCCUUAUGUUGUAGAUGAAGCUUGCUGUUUUUAGCAAGUUCCUGGGUUUCACAUUCAUUUCUGCUGCAUCUAGUAGCUCCACACAUUUCAUAACCUGAUCUCUUUAUUUGUAUGCAAAAAAUACUGUCUUAAUACAGAGCAGCAUUUUUGUAACAAAGAGACUCGCUGGAGCUAUUUGGUGCUUGAAUGUGACCAUCCUUUUUACUUUUGCUAAGCCUUAUUUAAAUUUUGUAUACCGUGGAAUAUGUAGAAUUUGUCAAAUCAUUUUAGUGCUGAAGGUUUUUGAUUUCUUGUUUUUGUUUCUGUUGUUGCAGUUUCUUUGGUGGCUUGUUUUGUAUUGUAAGAUGGCACUUGCUGAUAUAAAUACUAAGGCACUAAGAGAAAAUACAGAUAAGUAUUUAUAAGUUGCUUGGGAACCAUAGCAGAAUUUUUUGUUUGGUUUUGUAAGAGAAAAAAAAUUACCAAUAAAUAACUGAUCUAGCACCCAAACUCUCUUGGGGGAUGUCUUAGUAUCUUCACGCUAUAAAAUUGUUCAUCUAAGCACAGCAUCAUCUUAUGGCCUUAUGGAUUGUAAAUCUUCUAGUGAGGCUAUAAACUCCACUCUGAAAACAAAGGCAUAACUUAACCGACUGCUCAGUUGUCCUUCGUUGUAAAAUGAAUUGGCUUUGGGAAAAAGGAAAAAAACAAACAAAAAAAGAAAAAGAAAAAAGCCUCCUCCUUGCCCCUAAUUUUUUUUUCCCAUAUGGUUUUAGCCAUUCCCCAUCACUAUAUUGUGAAGCUGUAAAAAUAUAUAUAUAUACUUUACAAGAGUUUACUAAUGGAUUUCAAAACUGGUCUCAACGUUUAUAAUACAUAUCUGUGUUUGGCAGUUGUCAUAACCCAAUCCUACAUUCAGCCAUCGGGACAAGUCUGUCGGGGAGGUAGUUCAUGGUUUACAAGCCUUUGCUUUUUAACUGUCCAAUUUCCUUUAAAGCACAACUAGCUAUUUGUUUACAAAUGAUAUUUUUAUGUAUAUUUUGUAUAGUGUAUCAUCAUUUUUGCCAAAUAUGUUUUUCAUUAUAAAUGAGUAAAGAGUACUUAAGGUUGCAUUCAUGUAUUACAUGUUUGUUGUUGUAAACCUCUCCAAUCAGCUGGUAGAAAUUCUCCUCAUUGUGUUCUAUUUGGUCAGUCUCUGUGUGAUUGUAGGAUGUGCUCCUUGGUAGUACUCCCAGCUGUAGAUUUACCAGCUUAAAAGUUUGUUAGGAUCUGUGCAAUAAAGUGUUUGCAGUCUUAUUUUCUCUAAGAAAUUCCUUAUGGACGUCAUAAUUGUUGUAUAUUGAACAAAAUAUUUAUACUUAUGCAGUUGCAUAACAUUGAAAUAAAAAUUUAGCAUGAAAA